AUUAGGGCUCUGGUGGCGGCGGCGGCGGACCCUUGGGGUCUGGACGCAACGGCGGCGGGAGCAUGAACGCCCCUCCAGCCUUCGAGUCGUUCUUGCUCUUCGAGGGCGAGAAGAAGAUCACCAUUAACAAGGACACCAAGGUACCCAAUGCCUGUUUAUUCACCAUCAACAAAGAAGACCACACACUGGGAAACAUCAUUAAAUCACAACUCCUAAAAGACCCGCAAGUGCUAUUUGCUGGCUACAAAGUCCCCCACCCCUUGGAGCACAAGAUCAUCAUCCGAGUGCAGACCACGCCGGACUACAGCCCCCAGGAAGCCUUUACCAACGCCAUCACCGACCUCAUCAGUGAGCUGUCCCUGCUGGAGGAGCGCUUUCGGGUGAGGGCGGGGCCUGGAGGGGCAGACGGGGUGGGCUGGACACUGGCCCGUGUGCCCAGGCCUGGGACAGCCCUGGCCUGUUUCUUCGGAGGUCCUGGGGGAGAGGCGGCAGUGAUGGAAGAGCAGGGACUUCCACCACAGGCUCCAGGACAUGUGGACUGAGGGGCUGUGGAGUCUGGGCCUGUGGCUCCCGUCUGCCCCAUGGGACUUCUGUAGUGCUGCAGGGUCCCUCGGGUGCUGUGGGCCAGAUCGGGGCGGGGACCUACUGUCCUUUGGGGGUGCUCUUCUACGUCCCUUGUUGGUGAUUGGCAAGGCCUGGUCCUUCCAGGUCUCUGGGAGGCAGCUCACCCCCGGGUGGCCCACACCUGUUCCUGGCAGGGCGCAUGGGAAUCUAGAACAGUUUAGAGGGGAAAGAGCCACAGCUUGGGGGAUUUCAACGUCUGAGUCGUCUGCUCACCAGGAAGCCUCUGGGGCCUCUGACUCCUGCCGGGGCUGCCAUAGAGAAUGGCUGGAUUGGGCCAGCUGGGAGGGCCCUUUGGCUGCUCCACUGUCCUGGGGAGUGUGGCCCAUGGCUGCCCUCCAGGAAGGGCCUGGCGGGGGGGAUGCUGGGCAUGUGUUUCCAGCGUCCUUGCCCCAGCUGUUCCAGCUCAGUCUCCACCACCUUCUUCUCUCCCAGGUGGCCAUAAAAGACAAGCAGGAAGGAAUUGAGUAGGGGCCAGAGGGGGCUCUGCUCGGCCUGUGAGCCCCGUUCCUACCUGUGCCUGACCCUCCGCUCCAGGUACCACACCGAGGAGAGCGGCCGGUCCCAGCCAUGGCCCGCCUUGUGGCCACCCCUCACCCUGACACCGACGUGUCCUGUACAUAGAUUAGGUUUUAUAUUCCUAAUAAAGUAUAGCGGGAGAGACCUGGAUGUGGACUUGAGCAGCGGUGACUUCGCAAGCAAAUGGAUUGUCAGGCUUGAUGCAGGCAGAUGACCUGUUUCAGGGGCGUCCGGCUGGCAGGGAUGAAUUCAUUCUGGACCAAAGAUCCGGGGUCCAGGGGCUGCUGCGGGGGCUGUGCUGAGCCGGAGAGAAGUGUGCAAACCCAUGAGCUCCCAAGAGUCUCUGCUCUAGAAGCCUCAACUCCUGGGCCUGCCUGUCAGUCAAAGCAGGAACACUUCUUCCUGCAUAACUCGAAACACCUUUCCACAGGCUUCUUGUCCACAGUAGAGUUUAAUAAAAAUAUUCACUGAAA